CAAAGUGCCGGAAUUACAGGCAUGAGCCACCCCACCCAGCCUUCCCCUAAUUUUGAUAAUGAUAAUCCAAUGUUCUGUUCUGGCAUUUGUGUAGUUUUAGCGUGUGCAGUCUUCGAAGCAGUGGAGGUAUUUGCCUUUUCUUCUCUGUGACUUAGUCAUUCAGCAGUUCUAUGCUAAGGGUUUUUUUAUAUGCCUUUAGGUUCUUGUUUAGAGUUAAUGGAUAAUGAAAACAUUUCUAAUGCAUAAGAGAAAUGCAUUCUGAAACAAAAAUAGAAUACAAGCCUUCAGACAGAAGGCAGAGAAGAAACUGGAGAAAGAGAAAUAAGAUGUUAGGUAGGAAACCAUGGGAGACAGCACUGGGGAAAGUAACCUCCAGACUGGGAGUCACUGGGAAACCAGAUAAAUGCUCCUUGGCAGCGGGAGGAGUUGAGGACACUUCAGCUUGGUCUUGGGAUGGGAGCCCAGAGAACGCAAGUUGCUCCAACUAGGUAGGGAAAAUGCUGGGACAGAUGAAACUUGAGUGGCUAACAAGAAGUACCAGGAGCCAAAGGCUCUCUGAACACUUGGGCCUCUUUUAAAUGUCUGCCUUAAAUAGCUUGUACCAUUGUAAGUCUUGCAUAAUGGGUGAGAACAUGAACUUUUAGAAUCAAAGAUGUCACUCUAGGUGUGGUUGUAUUUGGAGUAAGGAAAUAAUUAAGGUUAAAUGAGGUCAUAAGUGUGGGGCCCUGAUCCGAUAGGACUAGUGUCCUUAUCAGAAGAGUGAAUGGAGAGCUUGCCCCUUACCCUUACAUACUGAAGAAAGAUUAUGUGAGGACUAGCAAGAAGGUGGCCAUGUACAAGACAGGAACAGAGCUGCCACCAGAGACCAAAUUGGCCAAAACCUUGAUCUUGGGCUUCUAGUCUCCAGAAUGGUGACAAAGUAAAUUUCUGUUGUUUAAGUCACCCAGUCUGUGGUAUUUUAGUAUGACAGCCCAAGCAGACAAAUACACCAUCUAUAUGCAGAUACAUCCAAAUCUCUAGUCUGUUGUAUGUCUGUACCUCUCCCCUGAACUUGGCUUUGUUCUCCACUUGCCUACUUAUUGUCACCACUUGGAUAUAUAAUAGAUGUCUCAAACUUCACUUCUCUGUAAACUGAACUCCUGAUAGUCCCCUCAAGCCUACUCCAUAGACAUCUUUCUCUUCUCUUUUUUUUGGAGACAGGGUCUUGCUGUGUCGCCCAGGCUGGAGUGCAAUGGCGUGAUCAUGGUUCACUGCAGCCUUGAACUCCUAGACUUAGGUGAUCCUCCCACCUCCGCCUCCCAAGUAGGAUGUGAGGGCAACCUGGCUGUGACAUCUCUCACCCCGUUGAUCACCAGGGUUGAUCCGGCUGAUCUGGCUGGCUAGGCCGGUGUCUCCUUCCUCCCUCACUGCUCCAUGUAUAUCCCUCCCGAAGCUGCACACUCAAGUCGAAGAGAACGACCAUCCCCAAUAGAGGAGGACUAAUCUUCGGUCAAGGACAACAAGGGAGGUGUCACAGUUUUCCAUUUAGAUCAACAACUUCAAGUUCUUACCAUGGAAAAUUCCGAGAAGACUGAAGUGGUUCUCCUUGCUUGUGGUUCAUUCAAUCCCAUCACCAACAUGCACCUCAGGUUGUUUGAGCUGGCCAAGGACUACAUGAAUGGAACAGGAAGGUACACAGUUGUCAAAGGCAUCAUCUCUCCUGUUGGUGAUGCCUACAAGAAGAAAGGACUCAUUCCUGCCUAUCACCGGGUCAUCAUGGCAGAACUUGCUACCAAGAAUUCUAAAUGGGUGGAAGUUGAUACAUGGGAAAGUCUUCAGAAGGAGUGGAAAGAGACUCUGAAGGUGCUAAGACACCAUCAAGAGAAAUUGGAGGCUAGUGACUGUGAUCACCAGCAGAACUCACCUACUCUAGAAAGGCCUGGAAGGAAGAGGAAGUGGACUGAAACACAAGAUUCUAGUCAAAAGAAAUCCCUAGAGCCAAAAACAAAAGCUGUGCCAAAGGUCAAGCUGCUGUGUGGGGCAGAUUUAUUGGAGUCCUUUGCUGUUCCCAAUUUGUGGAAGAGUGAAGACAUCACCCAAAUCGUGGCCAACUAUGGGCUCAUAUGUGUUACUCGGGCUGGAAAUGAUGCUCAGAAGUUUAUCUAUGAAUCGGAUGUGCUGUGGAAACACCGGAGCAACAUUCACGUGGUGAAUGAAUGGAUCGCUAAUGACAUCUCAUCCACAAAAAUCCGGAGAGCCCUCAGAAGGGGCCAGAGCAUUCGCUACUUGGUACCAGAUCUUGUCCAAGAAUACAUUGAAAAGCAUAAUUUGUACAGCUCUGAGAGUGAAGACAGGAAUGCUGGGGUCAUCCUGGCCCCUUUGCAGAGAAACACUGCAGAAGCUAAGACAUAGGAAUUCUACAGCAUGAUAUUUCAGACUUCCCAUUUGGGGAUCUGAAACAAUCUGGGAGUUAAUAACUGGGGAAAGAAGUUGUGAUCUGUUGCCUAAACUAAAGCUUAAAAGUUUAGUAAAAAUCGUCUGGGCACAGUGGCUCACGCCUGUAAUCCCAGCACUUUGGGAGGCUGAGGCAGGUGGAUCACGGGGUCAAGAGAUCGAGACCAUCCUGGCCAAUAUGGUGAAACCCCAUCUCUACUAAAAAUACAAAAAUUAGCUGUGUGUGGUGGCACGUGCCUGUAGUCCCAGCUACUUGGGAGGCUGAGGCAGGAGAAUCACUUGACCCCAGGUGGUGGAGGUUGCAGUGAGCCAAGAUUGCACCAUUGCACUCCAGCCUGGCGACAGAGCAAGACUCUGUCUCAAAAAAAAAAAAAAAUUUAGUAAAAAUCAAUGGUAAGCUAAAAUAAGUUUUUGUUUGUUUAUUUGUUUUUGAGAUGGAGUCUCUACUAAAAAUACAAAAAAUUAGCCAGGCAUGGUGCCGCAUAACUAUAAUCCCAGCUACUUGGGAGGCUGAGGCAGGAGAAUCGCUUGAACCCGGGAGGCACAGGUUCCAGUGAGCCAAGGUUGUGCCACUGCACUCCAGCCUGGGCAAAAAAGCAAAACUCCAUCUCAAAGAGAAAAAAAAAAAAGACCGGGUGUGGUGGCUCACACCUGUAAUCCCAGCACUUUGGGAGGCCUAAGUGGGUGGAUCACGUGAGGUCAAGAGUUCAAGACCAGCCUGGCCAAUAUGGUGAAACCCCAUCUCUACUAAGAAUACAAAAAAUUAGCUGAGCAUGGUGGUGGGCUCCUGUAGUCCCAGCUACUUGGGAGGCUGAGGCAGGAGAAUCGCUUGAACCUGGGAGGCAGAGGUUGCAGUAAGCCAAGAUCGUGCCAUUGCACUCCAGCCUGGGUGACAGAGCGAGACUCCAUCUCAAAAAAAAAAAAAAGCCUGACAGCUAGCAGGUUUCAGGAUCCAUCUGCCAAGUUAGUGAAAGGCUGGAGCCUCAAAUCAUACAGAUGAGGGUCAUUUUCUCCUCCUUAGCUUCUUGGAGUUUAAGAGUUGAAGGAGUCCUGAAAAGUAAUGAUAGAGCAAGAUGAAGCUAUCAGAACUGAAUUUGGACUUCCUCUGGGAAACUACACCUAGUUCAUCUGAAGUGUCACGUAAACUGCAGAAAGUUUCCAAUGCUGGAAACUUCUCUCAUACUAUCGUGCCUUCCUACUCAGAAGUGCCUGUGCCCUGCUCAGCUGUGACUACUGACCUCAGGACCUCACUGGACAAGGCAUGUGGGGACCCUUGCAGGAGCCCUGGUAAGGGUACAAUGAUCCUAUUGUUUUUUGUUUUUGAGAUGGAGUCUCACUCUGUCUCCCAGGCUGGAGUGCAGUGGUGCGAUCUCCGCUCACUGCAACCUCCGCCUCCCGGGUUCAAGCAAUUCUCCUGCCUCAGCCUGCUGAGUAGCUGGGAUUACAGGCACCCACUACCAUGUCCGGCUAAUUUUGUAUUUUUAGUAGAGAUGGGGUUUCGCCAUGUUAGACAGGCUGGUCUUGAACUCCUGACCUCAGGUGAUCUGCCCACCUCGGCCUUCCAAAGUGCUGGGAUUACAGGCAUGAGCCACUGCACCCAGCCUGAUCCUAUUGUUGCACUAUUUAUGGAGCAACAACUUUGUACAAAGAACAAGCUUUGUACAGAGAACAAGCUUGGCUUUUUCUCCCAACGCCGAGGAUGCUGUUGAUGCUGCCACGUAAUAGCAUAAUUUUGGGUGUCCUCAAGGACAGAACUUCCACUUUGAAUAAUGGAAGUUAGAACAAUGAAUUUCACAGGGGAAUAAAUAUUAAUGACUGACGUGAAGAAAAUAUGCCAUUGUUUAUUCCCUCCUGCAUCAUUUCCAUAAUUUGCUUUUGUACUGUCAAUUUAGAGGAAAUGUGUGAUGCUGGUGUUUUGUUUGGCCUGUUUGUUUGAUGCUGGGGGUUUUAUGUGUUGUACCCUUUACCCCUUACAUUGUGUAAUUUGAAAGUGGCAAACAAACCUGCAGUAAAAGUCCUUGAUUGGCAUCUUCAUUCGGAUGAUGGAGAGCCUUUGUGGUAGUGUUUGCUUAUGUGAACAGCAGGCCUUUCAGAUAAGAGAAGUGGCUUUUCCUUGGUGAUGAAGGGGUAGAGAUUGAGCCAUGGGGAUGGUUUAGGUUAAAGAAUGCUUUUUUUUGGCCAUCAUGAGGAUCUAACAACAGAGUAGAAGGAAGGAUGCCCUAGGUCAGCAUGCAGGGUGGUGGGAGGGCUUUCAUCUUCCUUACCCAAGCCUCUCUUUUCACUUUUCUAGAAGUCCAGAAGUUGUUAUAUGAUGAAAUAGCCUCCUUUAACGUUUAUUUCUGGGUGCCAACGGAGGCCCAUUCCUCUAACAUUCUCAUAAUUUUUCUCAAAGGCCUAUGAUCUAAACAUUUCACCACGGCAUCCACUCAGCUGUGAGGCUGCGUACACAGUCUCCACCUCUGAAAUCUGAACUUCGUUUACCAGUGGUGCUGUUUGAACUUCAUAAUGUCAGCACUUCCUGAACACUUACUGUGUGCUUGGCUUGUGCUCCUGAGUGCCUUAUAUCAUAAGGAAACGGCAAAAUCAGGGGACUGGUAUAAAUGGUGAGCUGAGCUUGAAUCUAAGCUUUGUCUUCAGAGCCAGUACCCCUAAUCUCUCUUUCUGUAAAAUAUUACUUUUCAAAGAAUGAAGUUGUAGCCAAAUCUUGAAAUUUUUCAUUUACCCUAAGUGAGGACAAAUAAAGCUUUCAACAACA